AUGGCCCGUUUCCUGAACAUGCGCAAUCACUUUCUAGCCUUUCCACACCAUCGGAAUAUUGCACAGAAGUAUGUCAGUCACAGGAGUCCCCGAGGGAGGGCGGUGGUACCAGUCCUGCUGGCGGCUCAGCGCGGCAGGACACGUGUGCGCUUUCAGCCGGGUCGCAGGGCGCUUAUCGCGGCCCGGCAGUCGGGGCCACGCCUCACCCCCGCCCGCGAACCCCGACCUGGGGAAACCCGGGGCGCUGGGGAGGGGCCACUGCGUUCAGCUCUGGCGGUCCACAGCCCGAAGCGCGGCUUAGGAAGUUCGUGUCAGCGCUGCCUGAGCUCGUCCCCUGGAUGUCCGGGUCUCCCCAGGCGGCCACCCGCCGGCUCCCAUCGUGACCUCCAGCCGCAGCGCCUCCCACGCCGGCCGCCGCGCGAGGGGAGCGCUCGGGCGCGCCGGGUGUGGUUGGGGGAAGGGGUUGUGCCGCGCGCGGGCUGCGUGCUGUGCCCACUCAAAAGGUUCCGGGCGCGCAGGAGGGAAGAGGCAGUGCCCGCCACUCCCACUGAGAUUGAGAGACGCGGCAAGGAGGCAGCCUGUGGAGGAACUGGGUAGGAUUUAGGAACGCACCGUGCACAUGCUUGGUGGUCUUGUUAAGUGGAAACUGCUGCUUUAGAGUUUGUUUGGAAGGUCCGGGUGACUCAUCCCAACAUUUACAUCCUUAAUUGUUAAAGCGCUGCCUCCGAGCGCACGCAUCCUGAGAUCCUGAGCCUUUGGUUAAGACCGAGCUCUAUUAAGCUGA